AAACCCAAGAACUUCACUCUCUUGGAAACCCACCCAGAUCCUCCCCGUUCUGACACCAUGGUCAGCUCCUGUUGUGGCUCCGUGUGCUCUGACCAGGGCUGCAGCCAAGACCUCUGUCAGGAGACCUGCUGCCGCCCCAGCUGCUGUCAGACCACCUGUUGCAGGACCACCUGCUACCGCCCCAGCUGUUGUGUGUCCAGCUGCUGCAGGCCCCAGUGCUGCCAGUCUGUGUGCUGCCAACCCACCUGCUGUCGCCCCACCUGCUGUGAGACGACCUGCUGCCACCCUAGGUGCUGCAUCUCCAGCUGCUGCCGCCCCAGCUGCUGUAUGUCCAGCUGCUGCAAGCCCCAGUGCUGCCAGUCUGUGUGCUGCCAGCCCACCUGCUGCCGCCCCAGCUGCUGCCGCCCCUGCUGCUGCCUGCGUCCAGUCUGUGGCCGAGUCUCCUGCCACACCACUUGCUAUCGCCCAACCUGUGUCAUCUCCACCUGUCCCCGCCCCUUGUGCUGUGCCUCCUCUUGCUGCUGAGCCCACUGCCCUGGCUCACGUCCCCCUUCACCACUGGCCCACAGAUGUAGACCCUUCUACUGUGCUGACCAUUAGGAUACAUGAAGUGGGGUUGAUGUCAUUCAAUAGGAUGGACCUUAUGCUUCCAAAGAGCCCACCACCAUUUCACUGACUCUGUGAGAACAUUCUGGUUCAUUUUAAACUCCCUCCUUUGCUUUCUUUUUCUUCUGGUGGUGGCACCAAAUGUGAAUUAAUUUGUAAUACACUAGCUAAGAAAUUAUUCCAAUCUUCUGAUUUCCUUAUUUUCUUUAUCACUUUAAGGUACAGAUUCUCCUUCUCAGUGAGGUAGAUAUUAUCUGCAGGACCAGUUUUGUCACUGAUGUUGCACCCUCAGAUCCAGCCACCCAAUUGUAUUCUGUGUUUCUCCUAGGGUGAAUUUCUUAUGCUUUGUUGUAUCUCUGCUUUCUAAUAAACUUUUCUGCACUUAAGAA